ACUCUCCUCCCCCGAGCGGCAGCGGCGGCGGCGGCGGCGGCUGCUGCGGGCGCUGAAUGAGAGACGGUGACUGUUCGGGUCGACGAGUGCUACUCUAGGCGGCGGCGGCCGUGGCGGUGAAGCGUGAGGCCGGCAUCGUCUUUCCGUCCUCUGAGGCGACGGCCGCGGCUGCACAGGUCGGUGGGCUCAGGCCGCGGGGCGGUGCGGGGGAGGGAGGGAGGGAGGGUGGGUACGCGGCGCCCCCCGGGCGGCGCGGGGAAUGGCGGCGGCGGCGCUGCGGAGUGUGGCUCUCCCGGCCGCGGGCCCCGGGGCUGCUCGCCCUGCGCGCAGGGAGGGGGCUGCGGAGCUGGGGCUGAGGCUGAGGGAGAAGGGCGCUGGGCGGCGCGCCUCCCUCGGCCGCGGGUUCUCAGAGUCGGAGCGGCCGUGGGGUCCCCGCUCGGGGGCGCCGUCCUGAAGCCGGGGGCGCUGCGACCCCUUGAACCCGCCUCGCUCUCCCUCUUGGGUGGCGGAAGCCCCCAGCCUCCGCCCGCUCUGUUCUGGCGCCCAGCGGCGCCUCAGUCUUCCUUCAGGUGAGCCCGAUCCCGGACCUCGGAGCCAGGACCAGCAGAAGCCGGGCCACACCCCCUCCCCUGGCCCUGGCGGCUGCGCCCAGAAGCCUGGCCGCAGAGUUGGCCGCCCGCGAACCCGCGGAGUCGCGGUCAGGGUGACCUGUUGCAGAGCGGCCCGCAGCCCGAGCGGCCCCCGCCAGCCCCGGCCCCGGAGGGGCUGCGUCCUGUGCUGGCCUCGGGCCGGGCGCGCGGGCCGGGUGUGGGGCAGGGGCCGCAGCCCCAGGUCGGCUUGCUCUACGGCCUGGAACCGGGCUCUAGAAAAAAAAGGAGAUUCCGAACGUAUCUCAUCAAACACUUGCAAAGCCGGGAGAUCUGUCUGCAAAUAUCCGGAAUUCCAUUGCAGUAUCGGAUUAGAUCGAUUCCUGUUCAAGUUUCUUUGAAGAUGACCAUCAGAAUUUUAGGAAACUUUUCAGCCCGUGUUUGCAGAGUAUCGCUGUUAGACAGAUCAUAGCUUGCUCAUUAUAAAGCCUGUUCCACUCAAGAUCAUUAUGCUUGUACAAGUGCUAUAGAACAAGUGCUAUAGAAUCAUACACAUAAGUGUAUUACUCUUACGGCUAAAUAUCUUAAUUUAGAAUUAUGAGGAAACUUCCAAAACUGAGCAUCCAAACAGUAUUAUUUUAACAAAGAUAACCUCUAACUCAAGCUUUGUAGGCAUGAAGUUUAUCAUGUAGCUUCAAAGGUCUUUUGAGGCAGAUCUAAAUAUCAAAAUGUAAGGGCAUUAAUGCCAUUUGGGAUAAACAAUUUCAGUGUAUUUAUUUUAAGCGUAGUUCAUUUUUUCUUUUUAAAAUUCAGCAUAAUUUUUGAACGGUAAGAUGUGCGUUUUUCCCAUUAUAUUCCACUUUUUUUUUUUUCCUUUUAAGAUAGGUUCUCCUUAUUUGGCUCAGGCUGGUCUCAGACUCCUGAGCUCAAGCGAUCCUCCCGUGUCAGGCUCCCAAGAAGCUGGGACUACAGGCAUGCGCCACUGUGCGUUAUUUCACUUUUCAUUGAAUUAAGGAAUUUGACUUUUAGUAAUACUUUGGGGCAGGACUCUGGAAAUACUGUUUAGUUUGCCUAAAUUUUUUCAGAUUGCAACGUAAGUUUGAAGAUAAUGCUUGCAUUGGCAGAACACAACGUGCUUUUCUAAUAUUUAUUAGUAAUACUAGAAAGAAUACAACAAAUUUUCCUGAGAGAAAACAUAACUGAAAAACUGGCUUUGUGAGUCAGAUACAUAUGUGAGUAAUAUAUUUUUGUGUGUGUUUUUAAAUACCUGGUACGAGUCUUUUUAUUACGUCAUUAGAGUUCAGUGUAGUGAAUGAUGGAUAUAUAGGUGAAAUUGUCCUGUUGCAACUUAAAACACUUAAGCUUUUUCCAGAGACUCAGUUCAUUCUGCACAUGUGUAUUGGGUACCUACUUGGUGCCAGUUAGUUCCCUAGAGGUUGGGGACACAACAGGGGAGACACAACAGGGCUUAUCAUUUAAGCCCUGAUGGGGCUUAAAUGAUAAGUGGGCAAAUAUGUUUGUUUAAAAGUUUAAGAAGUAGAAACUCCUCUGAUAACUUUUUGGUUAAGGAUAUUGUUUUUUUCUUUCUGAGAAUUGUGGGAAUUAUUGCCUAGCGAACAAAAACAUUAAGACAAUUGUUUUUAGAAUAUGCCUAUGUUUAUAUACUUUGGGUUUCUGGUUACCAAGUAUACCAAAGAUAAACAUUCUACCUGAAGUCAGAUGAUGCGUAGUUUACAUGUGGUUAGACAGCCUUAUUCUUUUGGUUUAUGUAGUUAAAUGAAUGUUUGCUGAAAAUAUUCUCUCGGCAUUUAUUUAUAAGGGAAUCUAAAUUUCUUUUUUGGUCUAAAAUUUUAAAAUAUCACCUUUUUAUUUCUGGCUGACUGUGAGUGAACCAAUUCCUUGAUAAUCUGCUUUUUCAGAAAUUUUUAAAUAACUUUUAAACCAUAAACCAAACUAUUAAUUGAAAUUUAUUGAAUCAAAUUUGUUUUCUUUUGUGAGUUAAACUUUAAACCCAUUUUCUCCGAAAGUAUGCUUUUUUUUUUUUUUUUGCUAUGUAAAAUAGGCACAUAGUUUGGGUUUACUUUUAAUUUUAAUGAUACACAGUUUGAGAAUAAGAUAUUGAAGUGUAUCCAUUUUUUGAAUAUGAGAUAUUUAUUGUGUAACGACUGUAUUUGGAAUAAAAUUGUCACUUUAAUAUGAAUACUUUUUUUUAAGUUAAUUUUCAAUGAAAGAUAAUUCAAAUAGCUUGAAACUACCCCAGCCUGAGUGAAGUUCCUUGGAGAGGAAAAUGAAUGUAUUGCAUUACCCUGUAAAUUGUUUCUUUAAAUGUGUCUUAAAUUUCCUAUUGAAUCCUUUUUAGUGAGAGAAUAAAGAUUGUGAUAAAUUUUAGUAACGUGGAAUUAAUCUGGAAUCUUUUUUGGUUUAAUGUCUUGAGCUUUUGAUUUAGGAAAACUUUUAACUACAUAAUAGAAAUAAAACACUGGAAUUUAAAAUGUGUUACAUUUACCUAUUCUAUGGAAAGAAAAAAGUUUGAAUAUAAAUUUACAUAGUCACUUUACUAAGUAGCUAGUUAGGGAUAUGGGAAGGAUCUAUAUAUACAUACAGUUAUAUGGAUAUAGCAGUGUUCAUAUGACUUAGCUUGAGGAAGCUUGGCCGUUUAUUUCAUUACAGAGAAACUUUUGGUACUGGCUUUUGAAUAAUACAUUGCUUUGGAGUGUGAAAGACUUGAAUCUCUCAUCUUGAAUUUAAUUGAUAGUUUUCUGUUAUUUCACUUACAUGACCUUUUUUUUCAGAACAGAUUUUCUUUAGUUUGAUUUCCUUUUGUUGUUCUUGCAGAAGUGUUUUCUGAAAACCUUAUUAAAUAGCAUCCCCCAUCAUACUCUGUGCCUUUGCCUUGCUUUAUUUAUUUAUUUUUACAUCAUUGGUUUAUCUGACAUUAAAACGUACAUUAGUUUAUUAUCUGCCUCCCUCUCUGAUUGUAAGCUUCAUGAGGACAAGGGCUUAUUUUGUACACUGUUCUCUUCCUAGCACCUAGAAAAGUAUCUGACACGUAGUGAUGCUCAGAUAUUUGUGGGGUAUUGUUAUUAAGUGAUCAAAGGACCCCUGGUUUUGUUCCUUUUUUAAAAAAAGAUUAAUAUUUGAUUUAUACAGCUGUGCAGUUAAAAAGAAAAUUGUACUACAAGGGUUAUACAGGUUGAGCAUCCCAAAUCUGAAAAUCUGAAAUCCAAAAUGCUCCAAAAUAUUAAACUUUUUGAGUGCCAGCAUGACUCUCAAAGAAAAUGUUCAUUGGAGCAGUUUGAGUUUUAAAUAUUUGGAUUUGGGAUGCCCAACUGGCAAUGCAAGUCUUCCAAAAUCUGACAAAAUCUGAAAUUCAACAAAAUUUGAAAUCUGAAUUUUUCUGGCCCCAAGCCAGGUACUCAGAUAACCUGUAAUUAAAACUCCGGUCCUCUGCCUCAUGUCUUUAUGACUUUCCCUCCUGUGUCCUGCUUUCAGAGCAACCAUAGGUGUUUCUUCUAUUUAUUUACAUAUUUAAAAAUUAUAUACUUUUACUGUUUGUUUUUCAGUUUUAUUAUUUAUUUAUUUAUUUUUUGAGACAGAGUAUUGCUCUAUCGCCCAGGCUGAAGUGCAGUGGUGCGAUCUUGGCUCAUUGCAGCCUCCACCUCUUGGGUUCAACUGAUUCUCCUGCCUCAGCUUCCCAGGUAGCUGGGGUUACAGGCAUGUGCCACCAUGCCUGACUAAUUUUUGUAUUUGUAGUAGAGACGGGUUUUCACCAUGUUGGCCAGGCUGUGAACUCCUGACCUCAAGUGAUCCACCCGUUCUCCCUGGCCUCCCUAAGUGCUGAGAUUACAGGUGUGAGCCACCAUGCCUGGCCCUGUUUUUCAGUUUUCCUGUUUUUCAAUUUUAGCUGUUGUCUGUUGGCUUUCUUCUGUGGUAGAUGAGUCUAUGCUUUAGGAUUCUUAUGCCACCUUGAAAUUUCUUUCCCAUGUCUUCCCAAUAUAGUCAUGCUUUUGAUUAAAUCAGCAUUCGUUGUUUACAUUAUUAUGAGUUUGUAAAUAUGUUUACAGUGGAACCUUACAGUGUACUAUGAUUAUAUUUCUUGGAGUUGAUUUCUUUUUAUUUCUUAGUUUCCUAUUUGUCUCUAAUUUUUUUUUCUACAAACUGUCCCAAUAUCAUCAAACAUCAGGUAAUUGACCCUUCAGUUUUAAAAAAAAAAAAUGAAAAUUCUUCUUGAACUAUCUUCUUGCUCAAAUCUGCACUUUUGCCUUCCACUUAUGCUGUGUAGCUAUAAUUGUGACUUCCCUUCAUCAUGAUUCUGAGAAUUCUGUUUUUUUUUUUGUUUUUUUUUUUGAGACAAGAGUUUUGCUCUUGUUGCCCAGGCUGGAGUGCAAUGGCGUGAUCUCGGCUCACCACAACCUCUGCUUCCCGGGUUUAAGCGAUUCUCCUGCCUCAGCCUCCCAAGUAGCUGGGAUUACAGGCAUGUGCCACCACACCCAGCUAAUUUUGUAUUUUUAGGAGAGACGGGGUUUCUCCAUGUUGGUCAGGCUGGUCUCGACCCAACCUCAAGUGAUUCGCCCACCUCAGGCUCCCAGAGUGCUGGGAUUAUAGGCGUGAGCCACUGCGCCUGGCUGAUUCUGAGAAUUCUUUUUGCCAUUUUCCUGUGAUCUCUGGAUCCAUAUCCUCCGCUUUCUUGAUUUACUCCUUUGUUUUGGUGAAAUGCAUCCUUUGGUAACUUUCAAGAAAGAGUAUAUGAAGAGGUAAAAUUUGUGAGAUGUGUGUAUUGCUGAAAAUAUUUUCCUUCUACCUUGACACCUGGUUGAUAAUAUGGCAGGGAUAGGUAUAGAAUUCCAAGGUAAAAAUCAUCUUCAAAUUUAGCAGAUGAUUAUACUUUUCUAGUUGUUUUGGUUUUUUUUUUUUUUUUUUUUUUUUUUUUUGAGACAGAGUCUCCUCUGUCCCCCAGGCUGGAGAGCAGUGAUAUGAUCUUGGCUCAGUGCACCCUCCACCUCCUGGGUUCAAGUGAUCCUCCUGCCUCAGCCUCCUAAGUAGCUGGGAUUACAAGCAUGCGCCACCACACCCAGCUAAUUUUUGUAUUUUUGGUAGAGAUGGUGUUUCACCAUGUUGGCCAGACCAGUCUCAAACUCCUGACCUCAAGUGAUCCGCCUACCUCGGCCUCUCAGAGUGCUGGGAUUACAGGUGUGAGCCACUGUGCCUGGCCUGAUUUUCUAGUUUGAAGUGGUUGUUGAAAAGUCUUAUGCCAUUCAAAAUCUUCAUCCUUCAUAUGUGACCUGGCCCUACGAUCUUUUGUCUUCAGUAUAUCUGCUAUGUCCCUGAUAUUUUAUGUAUCUUGUAUUGACUUUACUUUAUUUCUUCUACACUGAAUUUAGUGGGCGCUUUCAACCAGCAGUGUCCAUGAUUAUAUGGAGAGGAGAUAUGAUCUAGUUUAGAGGUCAGCAGACUUUUUCUUUGAAGGUUAGGUAGUAUUUUAGGCAUUUUGGGCAAUACAAUCCAUUACUGCUACUCAGCUUUGCUGUUGUCUAGUGAAAUCAAGCAUAAGCAGUGUGGGACUGUGGUUUGCUGACACCUGAUCUUAUACAAGCAGAAGGAUUAGCCUUUGCUUCACCAGGAGUAGGGAGAGUUACUAUAGAAAUAGGAGAGAAGACAAAGUAUAUGGAUAGACACAUGAUGGUGGUAGCUUGAGAACGUUCUCAUGAGUGUUUCAAUUUACCUUUGUGUAUAGAGGCCAAGCUCAUCAUCUGAGAGUAAGGAAGAAUGGGAAUAUGUAUUAGAGGUUUGAGAAGGAAUAAUACAUGACAUAGUCACUUGUCAAAGAGUAAAAAAGUGAAUAGAAGAGGGAGAGUAUGAUUGCCAGGCAGCAGUAAGGGCUCACUUGAGAUACAUGGUUCUGAAUUUUAUGUUCCUGAUUUAUUUUAUUUAUUUAUUUAUUUAUUUGAGACAGAGUCUCACUCUGUCGCCUAGGCUGGAGUGCAGUGGCGCGAUCUCGGCUCACUGCAACUUCCAUCUCCUGGGUUCAGGUGGUUCUCCUGCCUCAGCCUCCCAAGUAGCUGGGACUACAGUUGCGUGCCACCACAUCCGGCUAAUUUUUUGUUUUUUUAGUAGAGACAGGGUUUCACCAUGUUAGCCAGGAUGGUCUCAGAUCUCCUGACCUCGUGAUCUGCCCAUCUUGGCCUCCCAAAGUGCUGGGAUUACAGGCGUGAGCCACCACACUCGGCCAUGUUCCUGAUUUUAAUAGGAGUACCUUUAAUAUUUCAUCAUUAAUUAUAAUGCCUUACUAUUGGUUUUGAUAAAUAACUUAAGACUUUUGGUAGAUAUGAUUAAGAAAUGCUUUGUCAUACUAGUUUUCUAAGUUUUUUUUUUUUUUUAAACAUAAAAUGUUGAAUUCAUCAAGUGCUUUUUCUUUGCAGGUAGAGAUCAUCUUUUCCAUUAAUCUGUUAAUAGGAUGUAUUACAUUAAUAGAUUAUCUCCUGUUGAACCAUCUUUGCAUUCCUGAGUUAAACCCUAUUUAGCUGUGGUGCAUUUUUUCACCCACACGGCUGAAUUUGACUUGCUGGUGUCUUAGAGUUCUUUAAGAUCUACAUUUAUCAGUGAGGUUUACAUGGGUAUAUUUUGAAUUCAAAGUUUCGCUGACUUCAUGAAAUCAGUUGUAAAGCUUUCUUUUUUUUCCCCCAUUAUCAGAAAUAAUUCUGUAACGUAGGGAUUCUUUGUUCCUUGAAGGAACUAUAGAUUUAAUAUGAAAGUUUCUAAAACAAAACAUGGAAAAAUAUCUGUAUGACCCUGUUGGAGGCAAAGGCUUUUUAAACCAGGAUGCAAAAAGUACUAACCAGAAAAGAAAAGACUGUAUUUCAUUAAAUAAGAACAUCUACUCAUUAAACAAUACUAUUAAGAGAAGGAAAAGGCAAGUAACACACUGGAAAAGGUGUUUGCAAUACUUAUAUCUGUCAGAGGACUUAUAUAUAGAGUAUAUUUAAAAGUAUGCAAACCAAUGCAAAAGAAUCAGGCAACCCAGUUUUAAAACAAAUGGACAAAAGACUAGAACAGGUAUUCAGAAAAUGAAUUGUUCAGAUGGCCAAGGUUAAAAAGUACUGAUACAUAAUUUUUAGAAAACCGCAAAUUAAAACUACAAUGUGAUGCCACUGCAUACCCACCAGAAUGGUGUUAGUUAAAAAAUCUGAAAUACAAAGUGUUGGCAAGAAUGUAGAGCAUUUGGAACCCUUAUACAUUUCAAGUGGGUUUGAAAAUUGGUACAGCCACUUUGGAAAAUUCUUUGGCAGCAUUUGCCUAAAACUGUAUCUGUAUAUGCUCUGUGAUCCACCAGUUUCAUGUCUGGGGAUAGACCUGAUAGAAAUCAGUAUAUGUGUGCAUCAGAGGACAUGUACAUUAGAAGAAAACAUAGGGGUAAAUCUUUAUGACCUUGGAAUAGGUAAAGGAUUCUUACGUAUGACACAAAGUGACACCAAAAGCAGGAGCAACAAAACAAGCAAGAGGUAAAUUGAACUUAAAAAUUAAAUUUUUUGUGCUUCAAAGGAUGCCAUCAAGAAUGUGAAAAGACAAUACACAGAAUUGGAGAAAAUAUUUGCAAGUCAUAUCUAACAAGAAACUUGUAGUCAGAAUGUAUAAACACUCCUAUAACUCAAUAAUAAAAAGACAACUCAAUUUAAAAACAGGCAAAGGAGCUGAAUAGAAAUUUCUCAAAGAUAAACAAGUGGCCAAUAAGCACAUGAAAACAUGCUCGACAUUAUUAGCUAUCAGGAAAAUGAAAUCAAAACCGCAGUGAGAUACCGCUUCACACCACUAGGAUGACUUGAAUGAAAAAGUUAGAUAAUAAGUGUAGGCAAGGAUGUUAAGAAAUUGGGAUCCUCAUACACUUGUGGGAAUGUAAAUGGAUGUGGCUUCUUUGGAAGACCAUGUGGCACUUCUUCAAAUAAUUUAACGUAGCAUUACCAUACGACCCAGCAGUUCCUCUCCUAGAACAGCAGAUAGAGGUAGAAAACAGAUAAGUGGCUUAGGCCAGUAGCAGGGGUAAGGGGGUGGUAGCUAAAGGGUAUGGAUUUCUUUCUGAGAUGAUGAAAAUGUUCUAAAAUUGACCGUGUUGAUGGUUGUACCUCUGUGAAUAUGCUAUAAACCAUUGACUUGUACAUUUUAAAUGGGUGAAUUGUAUGGUAUGUGAAUUAUAUCUCAGUAAAGCUGUUAAAGAUAGGAAAAAUAAUCAGUGAUGUGACAGUGUUGCCAUAAUAUUUGAGAAGAGCAAGAUGCAGAGGGAUAUACCAAGUAUUUGUAUGAAGCAAACAACUCCGAAACCUUUAUGUCUGUAUGUGUUUCGAUGAUUCUGUAAGGUGGAAAAUGUUGCACACUAAAUGUAAAUGUUUGUUUUCUUGUUGGUCUAAAAUAGGGAGAGGGAGAGAAAAAAGGGAAAAAAUAACUAAAGGUGUUGAUUUAGAAAAAGGAUAGCAUGUAUAGCAAGAUCUCAGUUAUGUGAACUAUAAAUGUUAAAAAUGUUGAGUAGUUUGUGUGGUGGGAUAGCAGAUCUUUUUUUCUUUAUUAUUUUCUGGUUGUUUGAUCUUUUUUAUUUUAUAAUAGAAGUAGUUAAAAUGAUAUUAAGAGGCAAUAAAAUAAAAAUAAGUUAUGAAACCGCCAAAACCAUAGCAAACAGGGCAUGUCCAUAGCAGCUUCGUGAUCACUUCCAGCUGGAAACAACCCAAAUGUCUGUCAACAACAACAAAAAAAGGGGAUAAAUAAUUUGUGGUAUAGCCUUAUAGUAUAACACUGUACAGUACUGGAAAAGAAUGAACUAUAGCUAUACUCAGCAAACAUGGGUGACUAUCACAGAUAAAAUGGUGAGCAAAAGAAACCAGACACAAAAGAGUACGUACUCCAUGAAGUCAUACUCCAUGACUUCAUUUACAUAAAGUUUAGGGCAAGGUCAAACUCAUGUAUGGUGAUAGAAGCAUGAGCAUGGUGUUUAGGAGUUGGGGCUGGAAAGGUAAGAGGAACAACAAAGAGGGACCUUCUAGAGUGCUAGAAAUGUCUAUAUUUUCUUUUUCUUUUCUUUUUUUUUUUUUUUUGAUGCUGUAGCCCAGGCUGGAGUGCAGUGGCGUGAUCUCAGCUCACUGCAACCUCUGCCUCCCAGGUCCUGCUUCAAGCAGUUCUCCUGCCUCAGCCUCCCAAGUAGCUGGGAUUACAGGCACGUGCCACCAUGCCCAGCUAAUUUUUGUAUUCUUUUUUUUUUUUUUUUUUUUUAGUGAUGGGAUUUCACCAUAUUUGAUUGGUGGUUACAUGGGUGUCUACAUUGUAAAAUUCAUCACACAGAAUACCUUAGAUAUAUGUACAUUAUAUUUGUACAUGUAUCUCAAAAGUAAAAAAUGAAACCAUAAAAAAUAAAAAUAAGCAAAAAAAUUAUUGUACUUAUUUAAAAGUAUUUGUAUAUUUCUGGGGAUAAUUGUAUUGCAUUCAAAGAUAGUUUCUACUAUCAUUUUUAAUGGUAGCAUUGUAUUGUGUGAAUGUAUCAUUAUUUAAACUCUUGAGCAUUUAGGUUGUUUCUUUUAGAUAGUAUAACAGUGAUAGAGUUAACAUCUUUUUUUAUAGCUCUUCCUGUACUUACAUAAUUUCCUUUUGAUGAAUUCCUAAAAAGGGAGUUAUUUGGAGGUUAAGUAUGUUUGCAUACUCGCUUAUGGUGUACAUGUUUGUUUCUCUAUGCCCUUAAUCACUUGGCAGUUAGCUUUAAAAACGUAUAUAUGUUGAUGUGUUAUGUAAUAAGUGCUCUGUGUUUUAAUUUGUGGGUUGUUUUUUUUUUUUUUUUCUGAGACAGAGUCUCACUGUGUCGCCCAGCCUGGAGUGCAGUGGUGAUCUCGGCUCACUGCAGCCUCCGCCUCCUGGGUUCAAGAUUCUCCUGCCUCAGCUUCUCAAGUAGCUGAGAUUACAGGUGCCUACCACCAUGCCUGGCUAAUUCUUGUAUUUUCAGUAGAGUCAGAGCUUCACCAUGUUGGCCAGGCUGGUCUUGAACUCCUGACCUCAAGUGAUCCAGCCACCUCGGCCUCCCAAAAGUGCUGGGAUUAAAGAUGUGAGCCACUACACCCAGCCUUAAUUUGCAUUUUAAACGUUUUCAAUGAAAGUACUGUUUUCAUAUGUGUGAUAUUAUACUACUUUCUCCAAUUUUCUCUUCACAUCCUACCCAUUCUUUUUGCUCAAUCUUUUAAGUCUUUUAAUGAAAUAGUUAUACAAAAAAGUGUAUAGAGUCAGGUGCGGUGGCUCACACCUGUAAUCUCAGCACUUUGGGAGGCCAAGGUGGGCGGAUUGCUUGAGCCCAGGAGUUUAAGACCCAGCCUGGGCAAUGUGGUGAAACCCUGUCUCUACAAAAAAAUGCAAAAAAUUAGCCAGGUAUGGUGGUGUGUGCCUGUAGUCCCAGCUACUCAGGAGGCUGAGGCUGGAGAAUUGGAGUCCGGGAGGUCAAGGCUGCAGUGGCCAUGAUCGAGCCACUGCACUCCAGCCUGGGCAACAGAAGGACACCCCUGUCUUAAAAAACAAAAAGCAUAUGAAGACUAAUACAGUUAAUCCCUAACUUAAGAAAUUAACCAAUGCAGUUGAAGCACCCUACUAGUUCACAUUAAUGUGUAAGAAGUCUUUAUGUAUUAAAAAUAUUAACUCUUUGUCUCUUGUUUUACUUUUCCUUGUUUUAUCUUUUGUUACCCAACUUACUGUAUUUCAUUGAAUCUAAAAUGGCUUCAGUUGCAAGAUGCACUAUUUAUGUACAUCUAAAAAUAAGAAUAUGGCAUUCGAAUUUAAGAGGCAUCUUAAUUUCAGAGAUUUUAAAAGGUAAGAAAAUGCACAUCUAAGAAUUGAUGAAAUACAUGUAUUUCACUGUCUUGCGCCUUUUUUCUUUUUGAGAUGAAGUCUUGCUCUGUCGCCCAGGCUGAAGUGCCGGUGGCAUGAUCUUGGCUCACUGCAACCUCUGCCUCCCAGGUUCAAGCAAUUCUCUGCCUCAGCCUCGCGAGUAGCUGGGAUUACAGGCGCCUGCCACCACGCCUGGCUAAUUUUUUUGUAUUUUUAGUAGAGACGGGGUUUCACCAUCUUGGCCAGGCUGGUCUUGAACUCCUGACCUCGUGAUCCACCUGCCUCGGCUUCCCAAAGUGCUGGGAUUACAGGCAUGAGCCACCGCACCUGGCCAGCGCCACCUUUAAUCAGAUGAUCAAUCUCUUCUUUUGUUUCUGUUUCUACUGUGAGUCCUAGAUAGCCUUUCCUAUGUCAGAAUAUAUUUUAAAAUUCACCUAUGUUUACUUCUAGUAUUUUUAUGGCUUAAAUAUUUUUCAUUUUUAAUUCAUCUUAUUUUAAUGUAAGAUCUAAUUUUUGUCUUUUUACCCAAAUGGUUAAACAAUUGUCAAAAAGUUAAAUGACAUUAAUGAUUUUUUUUCCUUUUGAGAUAGGGUCUCACUCUCUCACCCAGACUGGAUUCCAAUGGCAUGAUCACAGCUCACUGCAGCCUUGACCUCCCAGACUUAAGUGAUCCUCCUGCCUCAGCCUCCCAAGUAGGUGGGACUACGGGUGCACACCACCACCCCUGGCUAAUUUUUUUGUUUUUUUGUAGAGACAUAGUCUCUACUUUGUUGCCUAGGCUUGUUUCAAACUCCUGGGCUCAAGUAAUCCUCUUGCCUCAGACUCCCAAAGUGCUGGGAUUACAGCAUGAGCCACCACGCUUGACCACAAUAAUGAUUUUUGAACAAGUAGUGAUAUGCUCAAAUGUGCUGGCUAGGAACACAAUAUGGCUAUAGAUUUUGGUUAGGUCUAGUCAAAAAUUAUCAGUUUUAUUUUCUAAUAGAUGGAUAUCUUUUUUUUUUUUUUUUUUUUUUUGAGUUAGAGUCUCACUCUGUCGCCCAGGCUGGAGUGCAGUGGCACGAUCUUAGCUCACUGCAACAUCCACCUCCCAGGUUCAAGGUACUCUCCUGUCUCAGCCUCCCAAAUAGCUGGGAUUACAGGCACAUGCCACCAUGCCUGGCUGAUUUUUUGUGUUUUAGUAGAGACAGAGUUUCACCAUGUUGCCCAGGCUGGUCUCGAACUCCUGAGCUUAGGCAGUCCACCCGCCUUGGCCUCCCAAAGUGCUAGGAUUACAGGUGUGAGCCACUGCCGUCGGCUAAUAGUUGUAUAUCUUAAAUUUGCAUUGAAAGGAAUGUGAAUGUCAAAACUAAAUUUCAAUUUUAUGUUUCCUUAAAUUUCUAAUAAGUAUCUACAUGUUUUUGGGAUCAGCCAUAUAAUUUACUAAGCUAAAAUUAAAUAAAUUUUUUAAGGAUAGACAAUGGUUAUAAUUCUUUGAUGAAAGUCUGUAUGAAUCUGGGCAAGUUACUUAAUUUGUUUAACAUUCAGCUUUUUUAUUUGUAAUUGGGUAUAAUAGUGCCUUCUCAUAGGAUCAUUGUAAGGAUUUCUUUUACUCUUUCUUUCAGAAUUUUGAAGAUCAAGUGUAAUUAUAGCCCAGAUUCUGUUGCAUCUGUGGUUAUUCUAGAUCUCUAGGGUUACUGGAGUAAAUUAUUCGUUAUACCUCUUCCAGUCCUGAUUUAGAUUUCCAGGAUUUGUCUAGAACAUUUUUUUGCCUUCUGGAAUUAGCUUACAUGACAAAUCUGUAUGUUUUCUGUUGCUUUUCUUAAGCUACACUUUUGUGUAUGUGCUGAAAUCUUUAUAGAUAGUUUAGGGGUUUGUAGGUGGGUGAUUAGUAAGUUUUUUCUUUUUUUUGCAAUUUUGAUAUGCUGAUAUAUUUUUGUAUGUUUUUGUAGUUUAGAUCCUAUCUCUUAAAGCUAGAGGGACAGGAAUAAGUCUACUUAAAGAGCAACAUUUUGAGGAUAUCUUAUGGAUAAGAAACUCUGCUUCUGACUUGCUUAUUUUGGCCACUGGCAUUUUUAAAUGUUUUCUUGUAAGCACAGUACUUGAGAGUGUUAUCAUAAAAGUAUUGUUGUUCAUGUCUUCUUGGUCAGAGACAGUCUUAUAUGUGAAACCACAGUAAAUAACAUAAAACAAUAUGUUGUUUUGUGUCAGAUUGAAGAGCAUUAGCAGGUCACAGAAGAAGAGGCUCAGUGAGGACAGGAGUGGUCCUUAAGGAAUGUGUUUCAUUUAUGUGGAAAGAACAUACUGAUUGUUGAAACAGCAUGACUCAAGAUGUGGCAACCAGAACUAGGUGUUGUUGGCACGAUUUGGAUUGAAGGGUUUGUUUGGGAUGUGGCGGGAAAUACAGUACCUUUGAUGAGGUGGGACUAAAUAUUCAGCCCUUAGAAAUGAAGCAGGGGAAAUUAGAAUUGAAAUGAUAGUACAUAUUGUUAUUCACUAACUUAGCGUGUCACUCUGUUUCCUUUCUUCAAGAGAUCCAAAAGGUGACAGAUAGAACUCAUUGCCAAAAGGUUUUUAAAGAUAACCACUUUGAAGGUUUGGACUUAAGGGAACAGGCAGUACUAAUUGAAGCCAUCUGUGCUGCACUUGUUUAUCUAAACAGUUUGGACAGCUGAACUGGCUGUAGGAAUGAAGUCAACAAACCUAGCCACCUCAUCUGCUUCAUUCCAAUAUGGCCUAACAGAUAUAGCUAUAAGGAUGAAUAGGGUCAUUGAUACUACUUCUAACUCUGAGCGGUAUUUGAAAUAAUAGAUAAUAGUGGGUUUUCCUCCUCAGUUGUGGUACUCUUGAAUGGAGUAUGGCAACCUUUGACUUAAUAAUCACUGGACCUGUAUUUCAUGUCUUGUGUGAUGCUGUAAAUUAUAUGAUCCCCUUAGUAACAACCAAAUUUUGUAUUUAUAACUACUUAACUACUAUAACUAAGUAGAUUAGAAAUCCUGGCAAGACUUUUGAGUCCCAGAGUAGUAGUGAUUUAUCUGAGUCAGUAUCCUAGAUAUGUCAUUUAUAAUUCUGGCUUGCCCACAGUUCCUUUGGAGGAAAUCUGCUUUUUCUACAGUACAUUGCAGAAGAACAGACCUCAAUAGCUAUUUUUUUAACCAUAUAAAACUGUAUUGCAGUGGAUUGGUCCAGCAGUGGGCAUUUGACCUAAGGGUUGCUAAUCCAUCAACCACCUGGGAAAAUUUAUAUAGUCAGUUAUAGAAAACAUGGAGUUAAUUUACCAUUGAACCAUGGGAGCUGAAGCUGCAAAGAUGUGUUGGUGUAGAGUCCUGUAAAACUAAAGUUUAAGGGAAUGGAAAGUAGAUGUAAGCAGAAGCUAUGAAUUACAGAAAUGAUAAAGGAGAUGAGGAAGCCAUUUGGUAACUAUAAAAGAGUAGGGCAUGUGUGCUGAGAGAAGUGCAAAAUUCUGAGAGAAACCAUGUGGUUUGAGAGAGAGGUAUGGAACAUGAGAGUGAAGAUUCUAGUUUCUGGCACUGUAGAUACUGUUCUUCCUUUAGUACUUCUGUGGCUCCUGCCCUUCUUGAGACUGCAUUCAUUCCUCCCCACCCCCAGGAAAGAUUGUAGGCUUUGGUGUCAGACAUUUGACAUUAGAAUUCUGGCUUUUUUACCAGCCCCUGCAACCUUGGGCAAAUCGCUUAAACUCUCUGUCUCAUUUCUCAUCUGUAAAAUGAGCAUCAUAACAAUACUUCUCACUGGGUUGAUGUGAGGAUUAAGUGAGAAUGACACAUGGAAAGCUUAGAACAAUGCUAAGCGUAUAACAGAUGUUCAAUAAAUAGUAUCAUAUAUGUAAUGAUAUUUGAGGUAAUUUGAUUUUUUUGCAACUAAGAGUCUAACUAUAGUUAAUCUCCUUACUGAUUCACUUGGAGCAGAGUAACCUUGUGUGGGAGCUGUGUAAACAAGAUAAGGUAUAGGGAGUUAGAAAAUAUUGUCUUAUACAGUGUGAAUAAUAAUACACUGAGCAUUUAAUAGAUGCUUGGUGUUCUAAGCAUUUUACCUGUAUUAACUCAUUGGAUGUUUCUGUUACUUUCAUUGUAAAGAUAUAGAAACUGAGGCACAGAGAGGCUAACCAACUUGCCCAAGGUUAUACAAUAUGUAACGGGCAGAAAUAGAAUUCAAACCCAGGUGGUCCAGUUACAGAGUUUUAAUUUUUAAAUAUCUAAUUCCUUUUCAAUUCUUUCUUUUUAAAUGAAGCUAAGGAGGAGGUCUCAGUUUGUUGUUACUGUUUCUUUUAUGUUUUUCUAGUACUUGCUUCUCUCCCAUUUUGACAAAGACAUAGUAUACCUCAGGUCUAGAAACAAGAUGUGAUUCUUGGUAAAGUUCCUGUACUGUACAUGAAGUGGUAUAUCACCUGAAGGAAGACCAUGGAAUAAUGUAUUUGUGGCCUUGGACAUGAGGCAGUCAGUCCUCUGUUGCUGUUAACAUAAGGUCAGGGACUGAUGAGGAAAGCAUGGACCUAAUGAACGGGCAGGCAAGCAGUGUCAAUAUUGCAGCUACUGCUUCUGAGAAAAGUAGCAGCUCUGAAUCCUUAAGUGACAAAGGCUCUGAAUUGAAGAAAAGCUUUGAUGCUGUGGUAUUCGAUGUUCUUAAGGUUACACCAGAAGAAUAUGCGGGUCAGAUAACAUUAAUGGAUGUUCCAGUAUUUAAAGCUAUUCAACCAGAUGAGCUUUCAAGUUGUGGAUGGAAUAAAAAAGAAAAAUAUAGUUCUGCACCAAAUGCAGUUGCCUUCACAAGAAGAUUCAAUCAUGUAAGCUUUUGGGUUGUUAGAGAGAUUCUUCAUGCUCAAACAUUAAAAAUUAGAGCAGAAGUUUUGAGCCACUAUAUUAAAACUGCUAAGAAACUGUAUGAGCUGAAUAACCUUCAUGCACUUAUGGCAGUGGUUUCUGGCCUACAGAGUGCCCCAAUUUUCAGGUUGACUAAAACAUGGGCGUUAUUAAGUCGAAAAGACAAAACUACCUUUGAAAAAUUAGAAUAUGUAAUGAGUAAAGAAGAUAACUACAAAAGACUCAGAGACUAUAUAAGUAGCUUAAAGAUGACACCUUGCAUUCCCUAUUUAGGUAUCUAUUUGUCAGAUUUAACAUACAUCGAUUCAGCAUACCCAUCAACUGGCAGCAUUCUAGAAAAUGAGCAAAGAUCAAAUUUAAUGAAUAAUAUCCUUCGAAUAAUUUCUGAUUUACAGCAGUCUUGUGAAUAUGAUAUUCCCAUGUUGCCUCAUGUCCAAAAAUAUCUCAACUCUGUUCAGUAUAUAGAAGAACUACAAAAAUUUGUGGAAGACGAUAAUUACAAGCUUUCAUUAAAGAUAGAACCAGGGACAAGCACCCCACGUUCUGCUGCUUCCAGAGAAGAUUUAGUAGGUCCUGAAGUAGGAGCGUCUCCACAGAGUGGACGAAAAAGUGUGGCAGCUGAAGGAGCCUUGCUCCCACAGACACCGCCAUCCCCUCGGAAUCUGAUUCCACAUGGACAUAGGAAGUGCCAUAGUUUGGGUUAUAAUUUCAUUCAUAAAAUGAACACAGCAGAAUUUAAGAGUGCAACGUUUCCAAAUGCAGGACCAAGACAUCUGUUAGAUGAUAGCGUCAUGGAGCCCCAUGCGCCAUCUCGAGGCCAAGCUGAAAGUUCUACUCUUUCUAGUGGAAUAUCAAUAGGUAGCAGCGAUGGUUCUGAACUAAGUGAAGAGACCUCAUGGCCUGCUUUUGAAAGGAACAGAUUAUACCAUUCUCUCGGCCCGGUGACAAGAGUGGCACGAAAUGGCUAUCGAAGUCACAUGAAGGCCAGCAGUUCUGCAGAAUCAGAAGAUUUGGCAGUACAUUUAUAUCCAGGAGCUGUUACUAUUCAAGGUGUUCUCAGGAGAAAAACUUUGUUAAAAGAAGGCAAAAAGCCUACAGUAGCAUCUUGGACAAAAUAUUGGGCAGCUUUGUGUGGGACACAGCUUUUUUACUAUGCUGCCAAAUCUCUAAAGGCUACCGAAAGAAAACAUUUCAAAUCAACAUCCAAUAAGAACGUAUCUGUGAUAGGAUGGAUGGUGAUGAUGGCUGAUGACCCUGAACAUCCUGAUCUCUUCCUGCUGACUGACUCUGAGAAAGGAAAUUCGUACAAGUUUCAAGCUGGCAAUAGAAUGAAUGCAAUGUUAUGGUUUAAGCAUUUGAGUGCAGCCUGCCAAAGUAACAAACAACAGGUUCCUACAAACUUGAUGACUUUUGAGUAGAAGCCUGAGAAAAAAAGAGAGGUGAACUGUUGCUUCUACGUGAGCAUGAGGACCUGAUAAAAGAGCGCCAGCUAUAAACCAUCCUGUGCCAGGAAGAGCCCAGAGGCUCUGUCUCAGUCGUUGGAGUUCUCAACCAAAAAAGCACUAAUUUCAGGGAAUGAUUUGAGAUAUUCCCAGAGAACAAAUUGGAGUUGCAAAACAAACUGCCAUGAACCAUGCUUCUUAUCUCAGAACUGACCUGUGGAAACCACUGCCUUAAAAGAAUGAAAGGAAAACCAACAUGAAACACCAAAUAGUGUGUGUGAAUCUUCUGGCGGUGCUGUGCUUGGAAUAGAUCGUAGCUAAUUUGCAUUUCUUUUAACUUUGUAAUAAUUUUAGAGGGGGGAAUUGCCUUUUUUAGAUAUGCUUUAAAAAGGAAAAACAUACUCUUGUGGAUUCCAUCAGGAGCUGGUUUUGAACCGAGGUGAAGAGACUUAGCAGGGAUUGUACCAGCAGCCCACCUGCAAGGUUUGUUCUCCCUCUAGUAGUCUGCAACCUCACUGGCUUUCUCACAGCAAGAGUGUAGGAAUGAGAAAUGUUAGUCAUGUGAGUUCUUGGGUUUGUUUGGGAUUGGGUGGGGGUGUUUGUUUUGUUUUGGAUGAGGGGAGAAUUUUUUUAAACACUAAACUUCUGAAAUGUAGUACUGUAAGGGGAACAUUAUUUCCUGCAGGAGGUACAAAGGCUGUGUGUUCAUUUGCCAGACGCUUUUUUUUUAAAUAGGUUCCAGAAAACAUGGUUGUUUCUAACUAGGGUUAAAGUUUAGCUUUCUAUAUGAAUUCAUUGUUGGACCACAGAUCUGCUUAAGUAAAGAGCUAUAAUCCCAACCUAAACUUUUCUGAGAUUUUACAAUAAUUAGAUCUUUUUCCAAGUUAAUUGGGUUUUCCCUUCUCCCAGUCAUAGGUGGUUUUUAUCAUCAAGACAGACUGAUAUUUUGUCAGGAUAUUUUCUUUUACAGUGUUUGAUGUGCAUAAUGCCAGAGUUAUUUUUUUAUUAUUCAUUUUCUCUCUUUUUGUUCAAUAUGAGAUUCAGGAUCAUAUUUGUUUAAAAGGUAACACAUAGAGAUGUAUGUAUAUAUUUUGUUAUAAGACAUACAAAAUAAUUUUAAGAGGGAUAAAGGUGAAAAUAUCAGAUUCUGGAAAUUUUAAGUAUCUAAACUUUAUACUUGUAUGAUUUACCAUAAACAUACCAAAACAUUUUUCUGAAAAUUUACUGUCGGUCUCUGACAUGAAACCGUAUUUUGUCAGUAGUUGACCAAGCAGUUUUAUGAGAACUCUUCUAUGCAAUGAUGCAUUUAAUUUCUAAAGUAAAUGUUGAAUUAUUAAAAAAAAAGUUUGAAGGUAAGAUGCCUUAGAAUUUUAAUGAAAAAUGACACUCAAACAAAGGCUAUAUGUCGAAUGUUAUAAACUCUUGAGACAUAAUGAAUUUUAGCAGUGGCCUAGAGUAAGGUAAUGCUUUGUGACUGAUAUCUACUAAUAGACUUCUGUUACUUUGGGCCUCACAUAAAAUUUCUCACAUUCGUAUUCUUAGAGAAUUUUAUACUUUUUUAUUAUAAGUAUUUUGCCCUUGAGUCCAUGAAACUUCAAUAGAAAAUAUUGCUUAUACAAUAAUUAGCUUAAAAUCCAUCCAAAGGAAAAGAGAAGAGCUUUUUUUGAGUGUUAAGUUUUUUAAUUUAGUAUUCUGUUUGGAAAAGAUGUUAAGAGUUCAAAUAUGCUUCUUAUGUAACAGAAAUACCAUUAUUUCUGGGGUUUAGUGACACAGGCUGGAGAGGACAAAAGUUUCCUGUCCUGAAUGAUUUUUCAAUUAAUGCUCUAAGCUUAACCCAUGUUGGGUAAUAGAAAGACAUAGCCAGCAGUAUUACUACGUAGACCUUGCACAUCUUACUUUUGUUUUGCAUUUUUAAAAAUUUCUUAAUUUGUUUAUUUCUCUUCAGAAAUAGCGUUUUUAACAGUGUAUGUGCUUUUUUAAAAAGUAUUGUGAAUGAGAACCCUGUGGAUUUUUUUUAUUUCAUUUGUUUGUCAUAAUAAGCUAACGUAGAAAUGUUGUAGGUUAACCAUAUCUGUGGAAAUAUGCAGUUGGAAGUCAGAGCCUGACAUCACAUAGUUUUGCCAAAGGGAGAGAGCUAAGCUGGAAGAUGUUUUUGAUACUUUCGGCUCUAAACAUUAAUGGAUGUUUGCGUAGAGUAAGAUAGCGUUCAAAUUUGGUUAAUAGUUUAUAGAUAGACUUGUGGCCUCUGACUGACUAAAUUUCUUAACAGCACAGAAGUCGUUGUUUUUCUGUCUUUAAAAUUUAUUCAUUCAGAAAAUUAGUCAUUGCUUUUUAAGAUUAUUUUAGCAUUUGAAGCAAAUUGAAAACAGAAAAGUGACUUAAAAUAGUGUAGGUGAAUUUUUUAUCUAUAAUUUACCAAAUAAUACCUGAUAAUAAUUCAAAGAAAAUAUGUUACCAAAAUAUAUUAAAUAUAUAGGUAGUUCAUUCGUGGGAAGAUGAAUCUUCUUAUUAAGCCUGCCCUCAAUUGUAAAUAAGUGACUCAAAAACUCAAAAUGUUCAUCAGCAUUCAGGUCAUUUGUUUCACCCUUAGCCAAGAAGAACUCAUUAGAAAUUCAGUUAUAAUUUCAAUUUAAGCCUGUUUAUGAUAAGCAUAAUGAUUGGCAUGUUAUAUAGCCUGUUGAAAAUAACUACAGAAUGACCUUCCAGAGCACUGUUUUUGGCCUCGUGCCCGCUCUGUUCAGGCUCUGCUUGUUUUUCAGAAUAUGAUUUUUACCUCCAGACAGUAAGAAUUGAACAAGAACUGAUCAAACACACCUUCCUAUUUUGUUUUCUUCACUAUGUAAAUAUUAUUUGGGCAAACAUUACAAAAAGGGAUCCAAACAAUUUGAGUUUCAGUAUUUUUUUCUCCCUAGGCAUGUGCUUCAAUUUCAAAUAUUUUUUUCUGUGUGGAAAAUGCCAUGUAACUAUUGCACUACCUUCUGUGUGGACUGUGUUGGUAUUGGUUCUUUCUGUAUAUCAAAAGUCAGGGUGUUUAUAACUGCAAAGUUUGUAUAAGUGGCUUUAUUCCUCUUCUAGAAGAUUUAUGAGGAGCCUAGGAAGCACUAUUGGUACAGGAGGAAAAAAGAAUGGAAAACAUGUUUACAGACUCUAGCUUUCCUUAUUAGCUUAAACUGGGGCCCUCAAAGAGCAGCCUGUUGAUCUUUUGGCCAAAUGACUUGAGCAUAAGUCUUUUAUUUCUUUUUAAGGUUAAAUCGUAAACUGUAUACCUUUACUACUGAAAACAAAACUAUAGGGCAUCAUACUAAUUGAAAAUCAAUAGUAAUGGGUUCCAUCCAUUAGCUUUUUAAAUGAAUAGAUCUGGUAUUGAUUUCCUUCCUGUUUUUUUGAGGCACAUUCCUUUACAACCAGUGUUUAAACCACCACGUAAUCAUCUUCUGCAAACAAGGGGUGCCAGUGUUGCCUAACAGAAGAUAAUCUUUAAUAAAGCAAAUCCUCUGCUUCAAAGGUUUUUGAAAUAAUUGGAUCCCUUUUUGAAAAGGAAGAUGAGUUUAACUGUGUCCAGGUGGAGUAAUAGUACUGCUGUUGCAUGAAUAGAUGAUACAAAGCAAGUGAUGAGGUUGGUAUGACUUCUUUAGUGACCUUUUAGGGUUUGCUUUUAUUUUCCUCUCUUUUUUGUAUUAUUUCUUUCAAACAUAGUAAAUAUAUGAUUUUACAGCCAAAGUGGUAUUCUGUUUUUUCUAAGCUUUGAGAUACAAAUAUUGCUAUUUAAUCACAUUGAUGAUGAAUUACUUUCCAUGUGAACCUUCUCAAAAUGAUUUAAGUACCUUUGAUUUUGCUCCCCUAAAAAUGGCUUGUGUCUAAAGUGACAUUUUUUUCCCUAUUUGGAGGGUUCUAAUGAAAGAGAUCCAGGCAUAAAAACUCUUUUGCUUAUUGAAAGCAAUUUGAUUACACCUAUGUUUCAGGUUAUAGUGGGGAGAAAAUUUGGUCAGUGCCUUAUUAUUUGAAGAGCAAUUUUAGGGCAUCAAGUAUGACAAUAAUCAUGUGCCCUCUUGCUCCUCUUAUUUCAGGAGUGUGUGCUAUCCCUCUCUCCACCAGCUUAAUCUUUCUCACCCCAAGUCUAACAAAGUCUUUACAGAAACCUCUGUAGGUGAUUGUUGCAGUCUUCCUUGGUUUUUGAGUCUUUUUAAACAAGCUCCUACCCUGCUUCUAUCCUUUUAGAGUAGGAGAUUAAAAAUAAACCCACCCCAGUCAACCUUUAGAUAAGCACUCUUAAAAACAAAUUUGAAGAGCACUCUUCAGCCAAGUUCAUUUUUAUUUUGUUGUUGAUGUUUUGAGCAUACAUUUAAUUGUAAGGCCUUUUGGAAAAGCCCUAAAAGAAUAAGAUACAACCAGAAAUAUUUGAGUUUUGUUAAAUGUACUGAAAUCUUGUAAUGAAAAUCCCUUUGGCCAGAAAUGAGAUUUAUUUCCAUUUAUUUUUACAUUUAAGUAACACUCAAAACAAACAAGUAGUCACUUAACCUGCCAGUUAUUAUUUUCUUGAAAAUAUACAAGAAAGUAAAAAUAUCUCUAAUAUAUAAGUUAAAGGAAAGUUAAGAGACUAAGCUAGUUUUUUCAGUGAAAGCAAAGUUGGAAAUAUUUUGCUUCUCUCAGAUUAUUGGAAGACCUAGAGCUACUGGAUGUUAACCUGAAUCAAGAUGUUCUUUUCACAUUUUUUUAAAGGGCUAGUAUGUUCCAGAGUAGGCAAGUAGUCAUUCAAGCCAAAUGAAAGAGUUAACUGGUCCUUGAGGAGUGUUAGCAAAAUUUAAAUUUUGACCCUGGCCAUUUGUACUACAGAAGUGAUUAUGGGAUUAAAAGAAUACAUAAUUACAGUGUUUUGGGAUUGGGCUCUUUUUUUUCUUAAUAGAAAAGCAGAAACUUCAUAAAUAAUAGCUGUGCUUUAGAUACCAGAUAACAAAUAUUGUUUCCCCUGAAGAUAUGACCUACUAGAACUACUCACAUAUAUAGUCCAAUAAUUACUGACUUAAUAGGUAUGGUAAAAUAGCUGAUAAUAAGUCAGACUCUCAAGAGUUUCUGUACCUUGAUUAUUGACAAAUUCAUUGUUUUACAUCCUACUAAAGAACAUGUGUGUGGGGAGGGGGUGGGGAACUGGUUCACAACAUAAUCUGAAGGAGAUCAAACAUCUGUAAGGACAGGUACCCAGUGAUGAUAAUAUAUCUGAAAACACAAGCCAUUUUUAUUCUUUAUCCCAAUUAACUUGAGGUACUCUAAUGAUGAAGCACUCGAUUGCACUAUGACCUCCUUGAGUGAUGUGCAGCUUGGUUCCUCUCUCACUUUUUGUUUCUUUUUAAUAUGCAAAUGUGAGUGUGCGAUCUUCAGUGUGUCUGCAUAAGCUAACUUAAGAUGAAUUUAAGUACAGUUUUCUGAAAUAUUUCUAUUGAAAUAAAUUACUUAAAAUUA